AGCUCCGCUCUGCCUCCGGCUCUGCGCUCACCUGCUGCCUAGUGUUCCCUCUCCUGCUCCAGGACCUCCGGGUAGACCUCAGACCCCGGGCCCAUUCCCAGACUCAGCCUCAGCCCGGACUUCCCCAGCCCCGACAGCACAGUAGGCCGCCAGGGGGCGCCGUGUGAGCGCCCUAUCCCGGCCACCCGGCGCCCCCUCCCACGGCCCGGGCGGGAGCGGGGCGCCGGGGGCCAUGCGGGGCCAGGGCCGCAAGGAGAGUUUGUCCGAUUCCCGAGACCUGGACGGCUCCUACGACCAGCUCACGGGCCACCCUCCAGGGCCCACUAAAAAAGCGCUGAAGCAGCGAUUCCUCAAGCUGCUGCCGUGCUGCGGGCCCCAAGCCCUGCCCUCAGUCAGUGAAAUUGGCCGGGUCUUCCGCUUUCUCGGUGACAGUUCGCUCCCUUCAGCAUUAGCCGCCCCAGCCUCCCUCCGCCCCCACAGACCCCGCCUGCUGGACCCAGACAGCGUGGACGAUGAAUUUGAAUUGUCCACCGUGUGUCACCGGCCUGAGGGUCUGGAGCAGCUGCAGGAGCAAACCAAAUUCACGCGCAAGGAGUUGCAGGUCCUGUACCGGGGCUUCAAGAACGAAUGUCCCAGCGGAAUUGUCAAUGAGGAGAACUUCAAGCAGAUUUACUCCCAGUUCUUUCCUCAAGGAGACUCCAGCACCUAUGCCACUUUUCUCUUCAAUGCCUUUGACACCAACCAUGAUGGCUCGGUCAGUUUUGAGGACUUUGUGGCUGGUUUGUCCGUGAUUCUUCGGGGAACUGUAGAUGACAGGCUUAAUUGGGCCUUCAACCUGUAUGACCUUAACAAGGACGGCUGCAUCACCAAGGAGGAAAUGCUUGACAUCAUGAAGUCCAUCUAUGACAUGAUGGGCAAGUACACGUACCCUGCACUCCGGGAGGAGGCCCCAAGGGAACACGUGGAGAGCUUCUUCCAGAAGAUGGACAGAAACAAGGAUGGUGUGGUGACCAUUGAGGAAUUCAUUGAGUCUUGUCAAAAGGAUGAGAACAUCAUGAGGUCCAUGCAGCUCUUUGACAAUGUCAUCUAGCCCCCAGGAGAGGGGGUCAGUGUUUCCUGGGGGGACCAUGCUCUAACCCUAGUCCAGGCGGACCUCACCCUUCUCUUCCCAGGUCUAUCCUCAUCCUACGCCUCCCUGGGGGCUGGAGGGAUCCAAGAGCUUGGGGAUUCAGUAGUCCAGAUCUCUGGAGCUGAAGGGGCCAGAGAGUGGGCAGAGUGCAUCUCGGGGGGUGUUCCCAACUCCCACCAGCUCUCACCCCCUUCCUGCCUGACACCCAGUGUUGAGAGUGCCCCUCCUGUAGGAAUUGAGCGGUUCCCCACCUCCUACCCCUACUCUAGAAACACACUAGACAGAUGUCUCCUGCUAUGGUGCUUCCCCCAUCCCUGACCUCAUAAACAUUUCCCCUAAGACUCCCCUCUCAGAGAGAAUGCUCCAUUCUUGGCACUGGCUGGCUUCUCAGACCAGCCAUUGAGAGCCCUGUGGGAGGGGGACAAGAAUGUAUAGGGAGAAAUCUUGGGCCUGAGUCAAUGGAUAGGUCCUAGGAGGUGGCUGGGGUUGAGAAUAGAAGGGCCUGGACAGAUUAUGAUUGCUCAGGCAUACCAGGUUAUAGCUCCAAGUUCCACAGGUCUGCUACCACAGGCCAUCAAAAUAUAAGUUUCCAGGCUUUGCAGAAGACCUUGUCUCCUUAGAAAUGCCCCAGAAAUUUUCCACACCCUCCUCGGUAUCCAUGGAGAGCCUGGGGCCAGAUAUCUGGCUCAUCUCUGGCAUUGCUUCCUCUCCUUCCUUCCUGCAUGUGUUGGUGGUGGUUGUGGUGGGGGAAUGUGGAUGGGGGAUGUCCUGGCUGAUGCCUGCCAAAAUUUCAUCCCACCCUCCUUGCUUAUCGUCCCUGUUUUGAGGGCUAUGACUUGAGUUUUUGUUUCCCAUGUUCUCUAUAGACUUGGGACCUUCCUGAACUUGGGGCCUAUCACUCCCCACAGUGGAUGCCUUAGAAGGGAGAGGGAAGGAGGGAGGCAGGCAUAGCAUCUGAACCCAGUGUGGGGGCAUUCACUAGAAUCUUCAAUCAACCUGGGCUCUCCCCACCCCACCCCAGAUAACCUCCUCAGUUCCCUAGGGUCUCUUCUUGCUUGACUCAAUCUACCCAGAGAUGCCCCUUAGCACACCUAGAGGGCAGGGACCAUAGGACCCAGGUUCCAACCCCAUUGUCAGCACCCCAGCCAUGCGGCCACCCCUUAGCACACCUGCUCGUCCCAUUUAGCUUACCCUCCCAGUUGGCCAGAAUCUGAGGGGAGAGCCCCCAGAGAGCCCCCUUCCCCAUCAGAAGACUGUUGACUGCUUUGCAUUUUGGGCUCUUCUAUAUAUUUUGUAAAGUAAGAAAUAUACCAGAUCUAAUAAAACACAAUGGCUAUGCA